GUCAUAGAAGACUACUCGGAGAGCGCUGCCUCUGGGUUGGCGGGCUGGCAGGCUGUAGCCGAGCGCGGGCAGGACUCGUCCCGGCAGGGUUCCAGAGCCAUGGGAGCGGAAAGGAGGCUGCUGUCGAUUAAGGAGGCCUUUCGGCUGGCGCAGCAGCCGCACCAGAACCAGGCGAAGCUGGUGGUGGCGCUGAGCCGCACCUACCGCACGAUGGAUGAUAAGACAGUUUUUCAUGAGGAGUUCAUUCAUUACCUUAAAUAUGUUAUGGUGGUCUAUAAACGUGAACCAGCUGUGGAGAGGGUAAUAGAAUUUGCAGCAAAGUUUGUUACCUCAUUUCACCAAUCAGAUAUGGAAGAUGAUGAGGAAGAGGAAGAUGGUGGCCUUUUAAAUUAUUUGUUUACUUUUCUCUUAAAGUCUCAUGAAGCAAACAGCAAUGCAGUGAGAUUUAGAGUGUGCCUGCUCAUAAACAAGCUUUUGGGAAGUAUGCCAGAAAAUGCUCAGAUUGAUGAUGAUGUGUUUGAUAAAAUUAAUAAAGCCAUGCUUAUUAGAUUGAAAGAUAAGAUUCCAAAUGUGAGAAUACAGGCAGUUCUGGCGCUUUCACGACUUCAGGAUCCCAAGGAUGAUGAAUGCCCAGUGGUUAAUGCAUAUGCUACUUUGAUUGAAAAUGAUUCAAAUCCAGAAGUUAGACGGGCAGUGUUAUCAUGUAUUGCACCAUCAGCAAAGACUUUGCCAAAAAUUGUAGGGCGCACCAAGGAUGUGAAAGAGGCUGUCAGAAAGCUGGCUUAUCAGGUUUUAGCUGAAAAGGUUCAUAUGAGAGCUAUGUCCAUUGCUCAGAGAGUAAUGCUCCUUCAACAAGGUCUUAAUGACAGAUCAGAUGCUGUGAAACAAGCUAUGCAGAAGCAUCUUCUUCAAGGCUGGUUACGGUUCUCUGAAGGAAAUAUCUUAGAGUUGCUCCAUCGGUUGGAUGUAGAAAAUUCUUCUGAAGUGGCAGUCUCUGUUCUCAAUGCCUUGUUUUCAAUAACUCCUCUCAGUGAACUGGUGGGACUCUGUAAAAACAAUGAUGGCAGGAAAUUGAUUCCAGUGGAAACAUUAACUCCUGAAAUUGCUUUGUAUUGGUGUGCCCUUUGUGAAUAUUUGAAAUCAAAAGGAGAUGAAGGUGAAGAAUUUUUAGAGCAGAUUUUGCCAGAGCCUGUAGUAUAUGCAGACUAUUUAUUGAGUUACAUCCAGAGCAUUCCAGUUGUUAAUGAAGAACACAGAGGUGAUUUUUCCUAUAUUGGAAAUUUGAUGACAAAAGAAUUCAUAGGUCAACAAUUGAUUCUAAUUAUUAAGUCUUUGGAUACCAGUGAAGAAGGAGGAAGAAAAAAACUGCUGGCUGUUUUACAGGAGAUUCUUAUUUUACCCACAAUCCCAAUAUCCCUGGUUUCUUUUCUUGUUGAAAGACUACUCCACAUCAUUAUAGAUGAUAAUAAGAGAACACAAAUUGUUACAGAAAUUAUCUCAGAGAUUCGGGCGCCCAUUGUUACUGUUGGUGUUAAUAACGAUCCAGCUGAUGUAAGAAAGAAAGAACUCAAGAUGGCUGAAAUAAAAGUUAAGCUUAUCGAAGCCAAAGAAGCUUUGGAAAAUUGCAUUACCUUACAGGAUUUUAAUCGGGCAUCAGAAUUAAAAGAAGAAAUAAAAGCAUUAGAAGAUGCCAGAAUAAACCUUUUGAAAGAGACAGAGCAACUUGAAAUUAAAGAAGUCCACAUAGAGAAGGUACAGAAUGAUGCUGAAACAUUGCAGAAAUGUCUUAUUUUAUGCUAUGAACUGUUGAAGCAGAUGUCCAUUUCAACAGGCUUAAGUGCAACCAUGAAUGGAAUCAUCGAAUCUUUGAUUCUUCCUGGAAUAAUAAGUAUUCAUCCUGUUGUAAGAAACCUGGCUGUUUUAUGCUUGGGAUGCUGUGGACUACAGAAUCAGGAUUUUGCAAGGAAACACUUCGUAUUACUAUUGCAGGUUUUGCAAAUUGAUGAUGUCACAAUAAAAAUAAGUGCUUUAAAGGCAAUCUUUGACCAACUGAUGACGUUCGGGAUUGAACCAUUUAAAACUAAAAAAAUCAAAACACUUCAUUGUGAAGGUACAGAAAUAAACAGUGAUGAUGAGCAAGAAUCAAAAGAAGUUGAAGAGACUGCUACAGCUAAGAAUGUUCUGAAACUCCUUUCUGAUUUCUUAGAUAGUGAGGUAUCUGAACUUAGGACUGGAGCUGCAGAAGGACUAGCCAAGCUGAUGUUCUCUGGGCUUUUGGUCAGCAGCAGGAUUCUUUCUCGUCUUAUUUUGUUAUGGUACAAUCCUGUGACUGAAGAGGAUGUUCAACUUCGACAUUGCCUAGGCGUGUUCUUCCCCGUGUUUGCUUAUGCAAGCAGGACUAAUCAGGAAUGCUUUGAAGAAGCUUUUCUUCCAACCCUGCAAACACUGGCCAAUGCCCCUGCAUCUUCUCCUUUAGCUGAAAUUGAUAUCACAAAUGUUGCUGAGUUACUUGUAGAUUUGACAAGACCAAGUGGAUUAAAUCCUCAGGCCAAGACUUCCCAAGAUUAUCAGGCCUUAACAGUACAUGACAAUUUGGCUAUGAAAAUUUGCAAUGAGAUCUUAACAAGUCCGUGCUCGCCAGAAAUUCGAGUCUAUACAAAAGCCUUGAGUUCUUUAGAACUCAGUAGCCAUCUUGCAAAAGAUCUUCUGGUUCUAUUGAAUGAGAUUCUGGAGCAAGUAAAAGAUAGGACAUGUCUGAGAGCUUUGGAGAAAAUCAAGAUUCAGUUAGAAAAAGGAAAUAAAGAAUUUGGUGACCAAGCUGAAGCAGCACAGGAUGCCACCUUGACUACAACUACUUUCCAAAAUGAAGAUGAAAAGAAUAAAGAAGUAUAUAUGACUCCACUCAGGGGUGUAAAAGCAACCCAAGCAUCAAAGUCUACUCAGCUAAAGACUAACAGAGGACAGAGAAAAGUGACAGUUUCAGCUAGGACGAACAGGAGGUGUCAGACUGCUGAAGCCGACUCUGAAAGUGAUCAUGAAGUUCCAGAACCAGAAUCAGAAAUGAAGAUGAGACUACCAAGACGAGCCAAAACCGCAGCACUAGAAAAAAGUAAACUUAACCUUGCCCAAUUUCUCAAUGAAGAUCUAAGUUAGGAAAGACGAUGGAGGUGGAAUCCUUUAAGAUUAUGUCCAGUUAUUUGCUUUAAUAAAGAAGAAGUUACCCUUGUCAAAAUCAGAACAAACCUGAUGUCUUUCUGAAGAUUUUCUGCUGUGCGCUUCCACGUUACUUUGGCCUGUAUUAAAGCAGUAGAGCAGCAUCAGUUAUUAUAGUCCAGAAAAAGUGUGCAUCAGUCAGUCACACAGAUUUAUCACAAUCUGAGGUGGGCCUAGGAAUCUCAUUUUUAAAUAGUCUCUCCAAGUGAUUCUUAUGAACUCUUUAUGUUUAAAAUCAUGUCAUUAUGGAAAACUUACAAGUGUAACUAGCUAGUAGCUUGCAUUUGAGAAGCUUAUGACUUAGAUGGGCAGAAUCAACAAAGAUGAAACCGCCUGAGGACACAUUUAACAAGUAACAUUUCUAGGGAAAAUGAAGGAAGUACCACAAACUGGCUAGAAAGGAGCUUAUCAAUCACCAGUGAGGAAGACCAGUAUAACGUUCAACAACAGUUAUUUUGACAAAAACUUAUUUUGUGAUUCCUACAGUGAAAACAUUUUUGGUGAUAUCUGCCUGGGAAAUCUCUCUUCCUAAAGUAUUUGUAUAUGGGAGUCCUUGUUUGUGAAUGUUUCCUGGAUUAGGGAGGUGUCAACAUAAAUGUAUUAUUAACCAUGAAGCUGCUCGCUAUAUUUUUGGCAUAACAAAAUAAUAUUUAUUUACUGUGGAUAAUAAUUCUAGUGGGAAUAUAAUGUGACAGGAACUUCUCUUUAUAUACGCUACCAAUUUAUGAGCACUAUUCACUGUCAAUUUCAUUUCUUGUCUUUUGAAAUUGACACUUGGCCUGACUUACGAAACUUGUACUAUAUGAAAUUGGUCCUCUUUUCUGCAAUACCCAACGAAACACCUUUUCUCUUUAUUAUUCAGAAAUGUCCUAACAUGGAUCUGUUUGUUUUAAUAAUUGUGCUUUUUUUAGGCUUAUCAUCUACUAGAGGCCAUUUACUUAAGGUGAAAUUUUAAGAUGGAGCUAAAGUAAGAUCACUGGUUUUUAGAACCAAAUUGCUAUACAUAUGUGCCUCAUAGAACUUAUAAAAGGAGUCAAAGUUUCAAAGCAAGAUAGUUAUUAAGCAAAAGGAAAAAUGGUAAUGAUAGAAAGUCAGUUAAAAAUAGAUGAUUGUUCUUCAUUCUGUUUGUUGGCUCUGUGUUCUCCUGUGCUUCAGAUUCCUUAUGUGUUGUUGUUUUAAAGACAAUUUGCAGGGGGUUGGGAGAAGGACUGAAAAGGUACAUUAAGUGUGCUGUAAGGAAAAGUCUUAGAAACAUAAUAAGCUAAAAUCCCAUUCACACAUGGCCAGGCUAUCCAAAAAGAAAGGAGCCAUGUUCUCAUGUGGUUUACCAUACCAAAGCUUGCUUUCUCUGGCAUGGGAAAAAUAAAUUUAAGCACCAAA